AGCUGCUUGCUUUCAGAGCAUAGCUUUCUCAACUAUGGCCCGGACGAAGCAGACAGCUCGCAAGUCUACCGGCGGCAAGGCACCGCGGAAGCAGCUGGCCACCAAGGCAGCGCGCAAAAGCGCUCCAGCGACUGGCGGUGUGAAGAAGCCCCACCGCUACAGGCCAGGCACCGUGGCCUUGCGUGAGAUCCGCCGUUAUCAGAAGUCGACUGAGCUGCUCAUCCGCAAACUGCCAUUUCAGCGCCUGGUGCGAGAAAUCGCGCAGGAUUUCAAAACCGACCUUCGUUUCCAGAGCUCGGCGGUGAUGGCGCUGCAAGAGGCGUGCGAGGCCUAUCUGGUGGGUCUCUUUGAAGACACCAACCUCUGUGCUAUUCACGCCAAGCGUGUCACUAUUAUGCCUAAGGACAUCCAGCUUGCGCGUCGUAUCCGUGGCGAGCGAGCAUAAUCCCCUGCUCUAUCUUGGGUUUCUUAAUUGCUUCCAAGCUUCCAAAGGCUCUUUUCAGAGCCACUUA